UCCGCCUGGGAGGGGCGCCCCGCCUGCCUCUUGUCAGAUCCAGUAGUGGGUCCCAGUGAGGCGCUUUAGCACGCUCUACCCCCACGUGUCCCGUGAAUCUGUUAGCUUUGCUCAUUUCUUCUUUGUCCCCCCUCACAUCUGACUUUUACUAACCCCAGUAUUAUUAAUGGGUGUCAUCUCAUCUUUUCAUCUCUCCAGGUUAUUCUUUGGUAACUUUCUGUUAGUUUUGUGCACCUGCGUGUCUCCUAAGAGCGGAAAGACAUAGUUGUGUUAGGCUUAAUUCAAGAGAGACCAGUGUUCCCAUUUUUAUAUUUAAGACUGUGUUUUGGGAGGGCGGGGGUAGGUAUUCGUGCAGUUAGCAACUCCUUUCGUGAUACUUAGUGCACUGAAGUGUCAGGGCAGUGCAGAAGGUACCUCCAACACCUGGCAGGACAGAUGUCCCCACAUGAGCAAGUAGUAUUCUGGUUUGGUAAUUGCUGGUGUUUGAUUUUACCAUUUCGCGUUCUUACUUUAAUCUGAUAACCGCUGAGGAUUGUUAUGUGAGAUAACUGAGGCUCUAAGAACUUAACUUCUCAAAGUUACAGUUAACUCUUCGAGUAAGGGGAAAGUCAGAUUUAAUAUCAAUGCUUAUGUUAUUUUUAUCAAAGCCCACCUAACUGAAUAAGGAUUUAGGUUAAACGUAUUCCCUCUGCAUCUCUUGGCAUGUGAGAAUUAAAUCUUUGAAUUGAAUGGUGAAUCUUGACUGUACGAGAAGGAAAAAUCUUGCAGGCAUCUGCCUAAUUACAGGUGUCUCACAUGUAUCUUCUAACUGCUUGCUUCUCAGAGUGUGACAAGUAGCAUAGGCCUCACCUGGAAGCUUGUUGGAAAUGCGGAAUCUCAGACUCUCCCACCUACUGAAUCAGCAUUUGCUUUUUAACAGGAACCUUUAACUGACCAGAGUGCUCAUUAAACGAUGAGAAGUAUUCUUUGUCAUAGAAUGAUUUGUUUGUCCAAGUUGAACUAAACAAGAGAAAGUAAAGAAUUUAAGAUUUUAUUCAUGUGCAUGGCAUAGAAGAUGAAUUCUUCCACUUCCACCAUGAGUGAAGAGCCUGACGCUCUAUCGGUAGUUAACCAGUUACGGGAUCUAGCAGCAGAUCCGUUAAACAGAAGAGCCAUCGUCCAGGAUCAGGGAUGUCUGCCUGGCCUUAUUUUAUUUAUGGACCAUCCCAACCCUCCAGUCGUCCACUCCGCUUUGCUUGCUCUUCGAUACUUGGCAGAAUGCCGUGCAAACAGAGAAAAGAUGAAAGGAGAACUGGGUAUGAUGUUGAGCUUACAAAAUGUUAUACAGAAAACUACAACUCCAGGAGAAACAAAACUUCUGGCCUCUGAAAUCUAUGACAUUCUUCAGUCCUCCAAUAUGGCAGAUGGUGAUAGUUUUAAUGAGAUGAAUUCACGUCGAAGGAAAGCUCAAUUUUUUCUGGGAACUACAAACAAACGUGCCAAAACAGUGGUUUUGCAUAUAGAUGGCCUUGAUGAUACGUCUCGGAGAAAUCUAUGUGAAGAGGCUUUGUUAAAAAUUAAAGGUGUUAUUAGCUUUACUUUUCAAAUGGCUGUUCAAAGGUGUGUGGUGCGAAUCCGUUCAGAUUUGAAAGCUGAGGCUUUGGCAUCAGCAAUAGCAUCAACCAAGGUUAUGAAAGCUCAGCAAGUUGUGAAAAGUGAAAGUGGAGAAGAGAUGUUGGUCCCAUUCCAAGAUACUCCUGUGGAAGUUGAACAGAACACAGAGCUACCUGACUACCUGCCUGAGGAUGAGAGUCCCACAAAGGAACAGGACAAAGCGGUGUCCCGGGUCGGCUCACACCCAGAAGGUGGAGCUAGCUGGCUUAGCACAGCUGCAAACUUUUUAUCCAGAUCAUUUUAUUGGUGACUUCACUUUUGGGCUCAAGGACUGUGUGAACCAACAAGGGGCCAGUUUUCCAUUGUUGUGGUGAACUGUCAAGUGCAAUUUGCAAUAAGUUAUCAUGAAAAGUUUUUAGAUUACACGAUCGCAUAUGCUGCAUUUCACGUUUUAUUGGACAUUUUACCCCACUGAGUGGUAAAAAGGACAGAGGCUACAGAUGGAGUUGCUUUGUUUAUGAAAGUAUUUUGGUUUGUUUUCUUUCAUUUAAUUGCCUCAUAUUUAAAAACCAUGGGUCCACUGUUAAAACCACAUGUGUAUGUGCAGCUUUACAUUUUAUUUUACGUGAAGCAUGUGAUUAGGAAAACUCAUUUUCUUUUCAAGCCUCAGGACCUACCUGAAGAGAAGUUUUCUUGUAGCUCAAGUUGUGCAUGAAUUACUGAAUAUUUUACUGUGCUUUUCUUCAUGAAGGGUACAUGCUUUGUACUCUUCACUGAAAGCUGAAAACAUUUCUUGUUACCCUCUUUUGUGCCUUUUUAUUUUGCCAACCGUGUUUAUAGAAAGGACAUUACUAAUGACAUUUUGCAGAUUAAAAACAUUCAUUUGAACACAGUAGUCCCCUAGAAAAACAACUCUACAAAAAUUUUGCAGCCUUAUUCAUUAUAAUUUUGAUAAAAUUAACACAAAAUCAGUCAAGAAGGAAACAUGUAUAUUAGUGAAGUGUUUUUGGAGACUGUUUGAAUGUGACCAAAUGUGGUUCUAGUUGACUUCUUUUCACUUUGGCUUAUAUCAAUUCUUGAGAGUUAAUGUGAUCAUGAUAUUGCAAACAACUAUAAAUGGUCUCUAGGCCUUACUUUGUGAUUAUACGUUAUCUCCGGCUAGAAAAAAAUAAUGGUAGUAAAGAAACUGACAAACUGAAAAUAAGAAAACAAAAAUCAAAUGCCUAUAAUACCAUAAUGCCAGUUUGGUAUAGAGUCCAACUUUAAAACAUGAAUUGCUCGACAGAGUUCUAUUCAGUAGGUGUUUCUUUGUAUUGUCUUUUGUGAAUUUAUUAUGAAAAUGCUGCGUUGUGUUGAAUGAAAAAGACCCAAAUUACUGCUUAUGAAGAAAUAAAGCCAGCAUUGAUCACUUAAUCCUGUUUCUCAUGUCCAGCCAGAAAAAAGAACUUCAGUGAAGGUAAGAUAAAUAAAUACAUACACAUAUGUUUUUUUGGUAGAUAAGUGCUAAUUACAUAUAUGUAAUGCUUUAUUAAAUUUCUGAAAUAUUUGGUAACUAAAAUUUUCUUUUUGGAAAUUAAUAAAUCCAGAUACAUAUUAAUGUUGAUAUGAGUAAAAACAAAUAGGAAGAAAUUGAAAUUUCUUUUCAUCAACAUGUAGAGCUGCUAUUUUACUAUUUGGAGAAUAUGAUGUGAAAAUUGGACCUCAAAGGGUUUCCUUGUGUUUUCAUUGUAAAAUACCAUCAUCAGUGAGAGUCUUGAGUUCACUAACAUUGUCACCUUCUGGAGAGAGAGUUAAUGGGGGGCAUUGAGGAUGAUAUUUUUUUACAUGUGUUUGGUUUCUGAUUCAAGUGACACGCACAAACUGAAAAAAAAAAAACAAAAAAAGCAACAAUAACUUUCAGGGCACCUAUUGCUCUAAAUGCAUAAUAUAACUUGCUGCCAGAACCAGAUGUGUUUAAAAAAGAAAAUAAAACCACCUUCUUUCUAUAGCCAUUAAAGCAAACUUUACUGUUCUAACAAAUUUGUAUUUUAUUUUGCAUUGCCACACAUCUGCUUAUUUAAAAACUACAUCCCUUUGGUAGUAAUGUUUCAGGACAAGUAGGUAUUACAGCUUGAUGUUUGUGUGUUCUAAUUCUAAGAGUUCUUUAUUCCAGAUCAUAUAGAGUAGUUAAGACAACUGUAACAGCAUUUUUUGAAAUACAUUGUAAAAUAAUAAAAGGUAACAUAAUUAAAAUCGAGUGGAUAUUA